ACUCGGCUCCUCUCCCCCCUCGCGCCCACAGCGUUUGGUGUUGAUUCGAGCGGGAAGAGGGGGGUGGGUGGGAUCGGUGGGGGAGACCAUGACCUCCAGCUACGGGCACGUUCUGGAGCGGCAACCGGCGCUGGGCGGCCGCUUGGACAGCCCGGGCAACCUCGACACCCUGCAGGCGAAAAAGAACUUCUCCGUCAGUCACCUGCUAGACCUGGAGGAAGCCGGGGACAUGGUGGCGGCACAGGCGGAUGAGAACGUGGGCGAGGCUGGCCGGAGCCUGCUGGAGUCGCCGGGACUCACCAGCGGCAGCGACACCCCGCAGCAGGACAAUGACCAGCUGAACUCAGAAGAAAAAAAGAAGAGAAAGCAGCGAAGGAAUAGGACAACCUUCAAUAGCAGCCAGCUGCAGGCUUUGGAGCGUGUCUUUGAGCGGACACACUAUCCUGAUGCUUUUGUGCGAGAAGACCUUGCCCGCCGGGUGAACCUCACCGAGGCGAGAGUGCAGGUGUGGUUUCAGAACCGAAGAGCCAAGUUCCGCAGGAAUGAGAGAGCCAUGCUAGCCAAUAAAAACGCUUCCCUCCUCAAAUCCUACUCAGGAGACGUGACUGCUGUGGAGCAGCCCAUCGUACCUCGUCCUGCUCCGAGACCCACCGAUUAUCUCUCCUGGGGGACAGCGUCUCCGUACAGAUCCUCGUCCCUCCCAAGAUGUUGUUUACACGAGGGGCUUCAUAACGGAUUCUAACGGAAGACACUGAAAAGCGCCAUGGCUACUUAUUCUGCCACAUGUGCCAACAAUAGCCCUGCACAGGGCAUCAACAUGGCCAACAGCAUUGCCAACCUGAGACUGAAGGCCAAGGAAUAUAGUUUACAGAGGAACCAGGUGCCAACAGUCAACUGAGGAAAAAAAAUAAUUAAACAGGCCUAAGAAGAAAUCAAAAACCAUAAGACACCUAUCCUGCUCUGUUAUUUCUUCAUCUGCUGGGGGGAAAAAGUAAAUUACAAACAAACAAACAAAGCAGAACUAAAAUAUUGGGACCAUGGCAGAGAAAAGCAGGAGAGGAGCAAAAUGAAAAUUAGUUAACAAAUGUUCCUCCUCCCUCUGGGAUACCACCACCACUUGUUUCUGUGUGUGUUUAUUUUGUUUUUCUUUCAUUCAUGCUUUGCUUAAUGUACUCCAGGCUUCUUCAGCUAGGUUCAGCCCACCCACCCCCAUGAUUGUAUGAAGUUUUAAAAAAAACUACAGCAGCCAAAGAAACUAUAUAUAUAUAUAUAUAUAUAUAUAUCCAGAAUGAUUGCCUCUACUGUCCUCAUUGACUUGUUUGAACCUUAGUGCCUUACCCUGUCCUCUUCCCAGUUCUCUUUAUAGAAGCUCUAGGAGCUUUCGAAAAGCCAAAGUCUUUCUGAAGAAUCUGUGCUGGACAGACAUAAUUCCCUUUCUCAUUGUCUCCAUCUUUGUUGGUCAUGGUAAGGUUUUUCCAUCAGCCUCUGAAAAAAUAGUUGUGCACAACAUCUGCUCACUGGACUGUCUGAUCCAAUGUAAUUGGCUGCGUCUGGCUAAUUCUAAGCACUAAAGUCUACAUCUAAGCUAUAGAUUUAAGCUUGAAGCUACAGAUUAUAUCACUAUCACCACCACCCCUCACCCUAUGCAAUCAAUCAAUCAAUCAUCUUAAGUUAAAGAUAUUUGUUGUCUUUGAAUGAUUUGCUGUCACAGACUAUUUGGUAGAAGAAAUAUUUUUCACCUGAGAGAGGAAGAGAAAUUUCUCUAGUAACACAAAGAGUGAGUUCUAAAAGGCAUGCCCACAUCUCUUUCGUGCCUUAAGGAUAGUGAGAUGCACACUUAUAUAUAUACUGUAUAUAUUUAUAUAUUUAUAUAUAUAUUUCAUAUAUAUAUAUAAUAUUGCAAGCUUAAGUUUGCAAUUUCCCAAACAAUACAAAAAGCAAAUUACACACCCUCACCACUGUUCUUAUCUCUAUAGUGAUGAAACAUUAAUUAGGGAUCUUGCUGCUUUUCUUUUUCUACACGAAGUUUUCAUUAAAGCCACAGAAUAAUUGAUAGGGCAGCUGUUUGAGAACAGGUCCCAUUUUCACAUUAGGGCUUUAAAUGAAUUAGAAACUAUUUGAGGCUAUAAAAAUGUCCUUGAGUUUGGAGCCUGAGCUCUGGUGAAAUGCUGAUACAUCUGAUCUAUCAUGGGAAUUGCAGUUAGAGAGAGUAAGGAAUACCAUUUAGUCAUCUAUCCGUUCUUCACUUAGCAGGAAUAUGAAAGAAAGGCACAUGUUUAAGAGGAAUACCUAAAGGUUUUUCUAAAUUCCAACAUUUAAAAGGCAAUUGUGGGCUAUUUUUAUUUUUUAAUAUUUUGAAAUAAAGUUUAGUGUCUAGGGCUGGGAGCCAGGACUGAUCUUCCAUUUCUUUUUCUUUGUUCCCAGCCAUGCUUUUGUAACUUGCCAGGUGGACUUGACCAACUACAUUACCAUGCUGUGCCUCAGUUUACCCAUUUGUAAAAUGGGAUUAAUAAUACUUACCUACCUCACAGGGGUGUUGUGAGGCUCUAUUCAUUUGCUCCUUUAUUCUUUCCUGUAUUCUCUGUAUGUCCAGCACUUUGUAGCCAUGGGAGGAAAGGGACUAUAAAAGUGUACAAUGUUAAUGGAAUGAUACGGUACCUGAAAGCCUUGUUUUCUAGUAAGAAAAUGCUACCUUGCUGUACAUACUUAUAACCUUGUAUUUGGAAAUGAGAAAUAGGUUUAUAUUUUCAGAUCUCUCAAAAAUCACAUCAUUUGACCAAAGAAUAAUUUAAGACACAUAGAACAGAUUUUUUUAAUUUAUAUUUUCAUCCUGACCAGCUUAGUUCUAAUAAUUUUUAGUUGUGAGUGAUUAAAAAACUUUGGAUCAAUUUUGGUCAAACAUGCCAACUUUGUAGUCUGAGUGACAGGCAAGGAUUUUUGGGUUUAAGAUGCACUUUUAGCACACAUUUGUAUUUCCCUUGGCAUAUCAGAUUGAGCUAAUGGUGAUGUUAUUUCAAUCUAACAGCCACCAAUCUGAAAUUGUAUUUCAAAUGUUGAUUCUGUAGUUCUUUAAAUAAUAAUGAAGCUCAUCUUAUACAUUUUGCUUUCACCAAUUGAUUCCUUCUUCUUUUAGCCCACUAUUAAAACAUUUCUUACUGAAUGGUUCAUGUAGGCUUGCUGAACAGCACGCAUUACUUGCUUCCUGAAGAGUUCCCCCAUUCAUCCAUUUGUCCCAUUAGUUGCUGUGGAUUAUCAAGUUUUGAAGGAACUGUACAUCCCAACAGACUGAAACAUUCUAAGUGAAAUGAGUAUAAUCCAAGUAACUGGUGAACUUUGGAGGUUUGGAGCUUGAAGAGAAUGGCUAAGAAGAUUUGAAUUAUAGGGAGGGAACAGAAAUCAUACAUGAAAAGGUUUUACUGAGAAGGGGAAAACCUUAGAUAGAGGGACAUGUGAAACAAAAUCAUUUGAAAUUUUGAUUCAGACAUCCAUUUCCAGUGGCAAACAGCAAAGCCUGAACCCAUAAACCCAAAUGAUAGGUGAAGUUGGGUGGUUUUAUCCAAUGUCUCAAGCAAGCAAUGUCUGGGAAUAUCAUAGAGUAACAAGUGCUGGUCAGCCAAAGAAACAUUCACUGCUGGUGAACCAAUACCAUAAGCAUGUAUUAUCUAAGCACUUGAUCAAGAAAUAUACAUGUUGUACAAGCUCUCAAUUUUGUUCAUUUAUUAUCAAAUUUUUAAAAUACAAGUUUGGUAUGUGAUUUGGAAAAGAUGCCUUCUGGAUCUUAAGCCAGUUGUCAGUGGAGGUCCUCAGGGCUGCAAAUGUCAAGACAUAACCCUGUUCCUCACCAUCAUGAUACCAGAUACAGGUGAAUACAUAGGAACUAUCUGCCUGUGUCCUCAAUCUCCCUUCAAACAAGAUGCUGAUUUGUAGGGUACUUGGCAGGUUAAAUUAAACCAGAAGAGGUGACUUAAUAAAAAAGGGAAUGACAUUUAGGGUAUAAAGAUCUCAUAAGAAAUGUAAUAUGUAAAUUAUAUCUUGCUUUAUGUUGUAAAAUAUACAUUGUUUGCGCUAGAAUAGAAAUGAUUUCUUUUCAAUAAAAAGAAAGAAGGACUCUACCAUGUCUUUUGUUAUAUACA